CAGCUCCCUAAGCUCUGCUCCUGCCAUGCUCCCCCUUCUCUCCUCGACCCAGGAAAGACGGUCGAGGUCGUGACAGCCCAGCCUAACACCGGCCCCUCCUUCCCAUGCAAGGGUGACUCAUGGGGCGGGGACCAGCCGCUCCUCCCAGCCCCUCGGCCUCACUGGGCGGAGGAGUGGUUGAGAGGCUGACUCCGUUUUCUCUGGGUUCCCUCCAGGGCCUGUGCAGCUGGACAGGGGCCAGGGCGCCUGCCCCCAACCCAGGGAGGAACCUGACAGUGGAGACUCAGACCACCAGCUCCAUCUCCCUGAGCUGGGAGGUCCCCGAUGGCCUAGACUCACAGAACUCCAACUACUGGGUUCAGUGUACUGGAGACGGCGGCACAACAGAGACUCGAAACACAACAGCCACCAACGUCACCGUGGAUGGCCUUGGACCCGGGUCAUUGUAUACGUGUUCUGUGUGGGUGGAGAAAGACGGAGUAAAUAGCUCUGUGGGGACUGUCACUACUGCCACAGCUCCCAACCCAGUGAGGAACCUGAGAGUGGAGGCUCAGACCAACAGCUCCAUCGCCCUGACCUGGGAGGUCCCCGACGGCCCAGACCCACAGAACUCCACCUACGGGGUUGAGUACACUGGAGAUGGUGGCAGAGCAGGGACUCGAAGCACAGCACACACUAACAUCACCGUGGAUGGACUUGAACCCGGGUGUUUGUAUGCGUUUUCCAUGUGGGUGGGAAAGAAUGGAAUCAACAGCUCCCGGGAGACUCGAAAUGCCACCACAGCUCACAACCCAGUGAGGAACCUGAGAGUGGAGGCUCAGACCACCAGCUCCAUCUCCCUGAGCUGGGAGGUCCCCGAUGGCACAGACCCACAGAACUCGACCUACUGCGUUCAGUGCACUGGAGAUGGUGGCAGAACAGAGACUCGAAACACAACAGACACCAGAGUCACCGUGGAUGGCCUUGGACCCGGGUCAUUGUAUACGUGUUCUGUGUGGGUGGAGAAAGACGGAGUAAAUAGCUCUGUGGAGAUUGUCACUAGUGCCACAGCUCCCAACCCAGUGAGAAACCUGACAGUGGAGGCUCAGACCAACAGCUCCAUCGCCCUGACCUGGGAGGUCCCCGAUGGCCCAGACCCACAGAACUCCACCUACGGGGUUGAGUACACUGGAGAUGGUGGCAGAGCAGGGACUCGAAGCACAGCACACACCAACAUCACCGUGGAUAGACUUGAACCCGGGUGUUUGUAUGUGUUUUCCGUGUGGGUGGGGAAGAAUGGAAUCAACAGCUCCCGGGAGACUCGAAAUGCCACCACAGCCCCCAACCCAGUGAGAAACCUCCAUAUGGAGACUCAGACCAACAGCUCCAUCGCCCUAUGCUGGGAAGUCCCCGAUGGCCCAUACCCUCAGGACUACACCUACUGGGUAGAGUACACUGGAGACGGUGGUGGCACAGAGACCCGAAACACAACAAAUACCAGUGUGACAGCUGAGAGACUUGAGCCCGGAACCUUGUACACAUUCUCUGUAUGGGCAGAAAAAAAUGGAGCACGUGGCUCCAGGCAGAAUGUCAGCAUCUCCACAGUCCCCAACGCAGUGACAAGCCUCAGCAAGCAGGACUGGACCAACAGCACCAUUGCUUUGCGCUGGACAGCUCCCCAGGGCCCAGGCCAGUCUUCCUACAGCUACUGGGUCUCAUGGGUCAGGGAAGGCAUGACUGACCCCAGGACCCAAAGCACCUCAGGUACUGACAUCACCCUAAAGGAACUGGAAGCUGGCAGCCUGUACCACCUCACCGUCUGGGCCGAGAGGAAUGAGGUCAGAGGCUAUAACAGCACCCUCACUGCAGCCACUGCUCCCAAUGAGGUCACAGAUCUCCAGAAUGAAACUCAGACUAAGAACUCAGUCAUGCUGUGGUGGAAGGCCCCUGGAGACCCCCACUCUCAGUUGUACGUAUACUGGGUCCAGUGGGCCAGCAAGGGACAUCCCCGGAGGGGGCAAGAUCCCCAAGCGAAUUGGGUCAACCAGACCAGCAGGACCAAUGAGACGUGGUACAAAGUGGAGGCCCUGGAACCCGGGACGUUGUACAAUUUCACCGUGUGGGCAGAGAGGAAUGACGUAGCCAGUUCCACGCAGAGCCUCUGUGCGUCCACAUACCCAGACACAGUCACCAUCACUUCCUGUGUCAGCACCUCAGCGGGCUAUGGAGUCAACUUGAUCUGGUCCUGCCCCCAGGGAGGCUACGAGGCCUUUGAGUUGGAGGUGGGAGGACAGCGGGGCUCCCAGGACAGAUCUUCAUGUGGGGAGGCUGUGUCUGUGUUGGGUCUCGGGCCGGCUCGGUCCUACCCAGCCACCAUCACGACCAUCUGGGACGGAAUGAAGGUCGUGUCUCACUCUGUGGUCUGCCACACCGAGAGUGCAGGGGUCAUUGCCGGAGCCUUUGUGGGCAUCCUCCUGUUUCUCAUCCUCGUGGGCCUGCUGAUUUUCUUCCUGAAGAGGAGGAAUAAGAAGAAGCAGCAGAAACCAGAACUCAGGGAUCUGGUCUUUAGCUCCCCAGGGGACAUCCCAGCUGAAGACUUCGCUGACCACGUCAGGAAGAAUGAGAGGGACAGCAACUGUGGUUUUGCAGACGAGUACCAGCAACUCUCCCUGGUGGGCCACAGCCAGUCUCAGAUGGUGGCUUCGGCUUCAGAGAACAACGCCAAGAACCGCUACAGAAAUGUGCUGCCCUAUGACUGGUCCCGGGUGCCCCUGAAGCCCAUCCAUGAGGAGCCAGGCUCUGACUACAUCAAUGCCAGCUUCAUGCCCGGUCUCUGGAGCCCCCAGGAGUUCAUUGCAACCCAGGGUCCCCUGCCACAGACAGUGGGUGACUUCUGGCGCCUGGUGUGGGAACAGCAGAGCCACACCCUGGUCAUGCUGACCAACUGCAUGGAGGCCGGCCGGGUGAAGUGUGAGCAUUACUGGCCUCUGGACUCGCAGCCCUGCACCCAUGGGCACCUGCGGGUAACCCUGGUAGGUGAGGAAGUGAUGGAGAACUGGACGGUGCGGGAACUGCUGCUCCUCCAGGUGGAGGAGCAGAAGACACUGUCUGUGCGCCAAUUCCACUACCAGGCCUGGCCGGAUCACGGCGUUCCCUCCUCCCCAGACACCUUGCUGGCUUUCUGGAGGAUGCUUCGGCAGUGGCUGGAUCAGACCAUGGAGGGAGGCCCACCCAUUGUGCACUGCAGUGCUGGCGUGGGUCGCACAGGAACCCUCAUUGCCCUGGACGUCCUGCUCCGGCAGCUGCAGUCCGAGGGUCUCCUUGGGCCCUUCAGCUUUGUAAGGAAGAUGAGAGAGAGUCGGCCGUUGAUGGUGCAGACUGAGGCUCAGUACGUAUUCCUGCAUCAGUGCAUCCUGCGGUUCCUCCAACAGUCAGCCCAGGCCCCAGCCGAGAAGGAAGUCCCGUAUGAGGAUGUCGAAAACCUCAUCUACGAGAACGUGGCCGCCAUCCAGGCCCACAAGUUGGAGGUCUAAGUGACGAGGGGGCUGGGUCGGCAGCCCAGGCAUCCUCAAGCUCUGGACACCCACUUGAGCCCAGAUUCCUGGAAGAGCAGAGGGCUGGGCUCCCAGACUCCUGGGUGCUGUGGGAGGAGGGGGCUGGUAUCCCAAACUCUGGUUUCCCCAGGAGAGAGUGGUCUGGUGGGCUUCAGAUGAGUCCUAUGGGAGCUGGGGAUCUGGAUUCCUGGUUCCCUGAAGGAGGAGAGGGAUGAUAGCUUGGAUUCCCUAGGUCUUUCCAGGAUGCAGAAAGAAACAGGCUGGGGCCUGGAUUCUGAGGCAGGAAGGAAUUUGGGUCUGGAGUUCUGGCUACUUGAGGACCAAAGGCAGGAAGGAUCCUGCCUUGAUUUUACUUCAGAAACCAAAUCAGUCUUCUAUAAUCUGGGGUCGGAGGGAGUCCCUGUGCCCAAGGUCUCUCUGCACCCCACCAUCCACAUGUAUUUUUCCUUCUAUCCCAUAAUUUAUUAAAUCACUGUUCUCCCCAGA